AUGGCCAGAAGGCGGGGAGCCAGAGGCGCCAGGACCCUCGCGUGGCGCUCCAGCACCCCAGACCGUGGCGGCGCCUCGCCUUAGGGAAGAGCAAGGGAAGAACUUUAUUUGAACCGCGAACAUUUUUUGGUCACUGAGAUCGAGUCUCCCAGUGCUUUGGCUUCCCGCCUCUUUAUCGUGGGUUUGAUCCCUGAGCUGCUCUCCUUUCCCGAACCUCCCGGGGUGCAGCCUAGAGCCCUCCCGCGCGGCUGACUCCAGAGUAGAGGAAGGGAGGCGGCCUCCGGCUGGUCCCCCGAAGCCCUCGCUGCCCCGCAGAUGCGGAUGGCCAGCCAGUAGCGGGCGGUGGCCCCGCGUCCCGGGAGCGCACAGCAAUGCAGGCGCUUAACAUUACCCCGGAGCAGUUCUCUCGGCUGCUGCGGGACCACAACCUGACGCGGGAGCAGUUCAUCGCUCUGUACCGGCUGCGACCGCUCGUCUACACCCCAGAGCUGCCGGGACGCGCCAAGCUGGCCCUCGUGCUCACCGGCGUGCUCAUCUUCGCCCUGGCGCUCUUUGGCAAUGCUCUGGUGUUCUACGUGGUGACCCGCAGCAAGGCCAUGCGCACCGUCACCAACAUCUUUAUCUGCUCCUUGGCGCUCAGUGACCUGCUCAUCACCUUCUUCUGCAUUCCCGUCACCAUGCUCCAGAACAUUUCCGACAACUGGCUGGGGGGUGCUUUCAUUUGCAAGAUGGUGCCAUUUGUCCAGUCUACCGCUGUUGUGACAGAAAUCCUCACUAUGACCUGCAUUGCUGUGGAAAGGCACCAGGGACUUGUGCAUCCUUUUAAAAUGAAGUGGCAAUACACCAACCGAAGGGCUUUCACAAUGCUAGGUGUGGUCUGGCUGGUGGCAGUCAUCGUAGGAUCACCCAUGUGGCACGUGCAACAACUUGAGGCUUUACCCUGAAUAGAAAUAUAUUUAAGAGAGAGAAGAGCACAAAGCCCUGCCAUGUGUUUAUGAUGCCUUGAUCAAUGUGGCUUCACUGACAUCAGUCAUUGAAUUAUGUCUUGUUUUGGUGCCCCGUGGUAAGAUUCAUUAUGGGUGAGAGAUGUGAUUUCUGUAACUUGGGAAAAGGGUGAUUAUGAAACAGGAAGUGGGAAUUUAGACCCAGCGUGACACUUCAAACUUGGGGACGAUAUUAGGCAGUGGAAUUUUAGAGAAGUGUAUGUUUGGAAAUAGAAGAUCUGAAAUUGAAGAUCAAAGAUCUGAAAUUUUCCAUAAAACCAUCUGAGCAUACCCUCAGGAAGUCUUUGCUGAAGUCCACAGUCAGGACUUUGCUGAAGUCAGGAAGUCCGUAGUCCCUAGGGCUAUGUGAACCUGAUCCAAGACUUCCAGUUCAGCAUGCUCUUAGAUGUGUCAGUCCAUACCCCCUGGUCAUUGGCCUUUGCAUGCUUUGCUUCCAUGGAGUUGGAAUGAAUUUCAUUUUAACAUCCUAUUUCCAGAGAGUUUGAAUCUUGAGAUUAUUUUUCAGUGAGUGUUAUUCCUAGUUGCAUCUGUAAGUAACACCUAGGUCAGAACUUGAAUUUUCUUACCUUUGAUGAGUAACCAAAAAGUUGCUGUCCCUCAUUCAAUUCACAUUGAAGACUGGUGAUAAAAUUUCCUGGGAAUGUAGGCAGAAAUAUGUCUGAGACCCAAGUAUUCAGCUCCACAGUAACUAAAAUAACAAUGGUUUUGAUAAAUAUUCUCGUUUUUAUUCCUAUUACCCAAAAAAGUGACUUCUGAAUAUGCUUUAAAUAUUUAGUUUGUUCUUGAACUAGCCCUUAAAGCACUCUCUAUUAUUUAUUAUUGUUGUUAAUAAUACUUUUGAGCUUAUAAGAUGAGUCUACCAGAAAUAGUACGAAUAAACCAGCAGGUACAAUCUGAAUAUUUGUAUAUUGGCAAUAGUUUGAAUCCCAAUUUCUCAUUCAUCUCAGGAUAAAAGCUGCCAGUUGCCUCUUUAAUAUCUUUCUAAGCAAUCUGAUCAUUGCAAUAUAUGAAGUAGCAGUAACAAAACGCAGCUUUCAGUACUUUUCAAUUGAAAGAUGUCUCAUGCCUUGUCAAAAAUCUGUCUCAACAAUUGAAGAAGCAAAAUAAUUUAAUAUUAGACUACCUAGCAUGUAUUGCAAAAUAUUUUUCAGUAUAUACUUUGGCAAAUAUAGUGCUCUUUCAGUCGAUUGAAAACUUGUGACUAGUGGAAAUAGAAGUUGAGAAAGACAAUAAAUGAAAGUAAACAGGCUAUGGACCUGAAUUCCAUUUAGAAUAGAAAAGCUGGUAUAAAACUCUUAAGAACUUAAGCAGUGAAGUGGAAAAACUAUGCUUCACAACAAAAGAACAAUUAAAAAUGUAUCUCAUUUGAAAUACGUGCUGGGGACAAAUUUGAAAGAACUUAAAAAAUGUUGUGUUGCAAUAAUACUUGGCUGAUUUCUGUUUUUUGAUGCUGACUACUGGUUCUUUUAAUGAAUUAUUCUU